GUGGCGCAGCUUCUCCGCCCGAGCCGCGCGCGGAGCUGCCGGGGGCUCCUUAGCACCCGGGCGCCGGGGCCCUCGCCCUUCCGCAGCCUUCACUCCAGCCCUCUGCUCCCGCACGCCAUGAAGUCGCCGUUCUACCGCUGCCAGAACACCACCUCUGUGGAAAAAGGCAACUCGGCGGUGAUGGGCGGGGUGCUCUUCAGCACCGGCCUCCUGGGCAACCUGCUGGCCCUGGGGCUGCUGGCGCGCUCGGGGCUGGGGUGGUGCUCGCGGCGUCCACUGCGCCCGCUGCCCUCGGUCUUCUACAUGCUGGUGUGUGGCCUGACGGUCACCGACUUGCUGGGCAAGUGCCUCCUAAGCCCGGUGGUGCUGGCUGCCUACGCUCAGAACCGGAGUCUGCGGGUGCUUGCGCCCGCAUUGGACAACUCGUUGUGCCAAGCCUUCGCCUUCUUCAUGUCCUUCUUUGGGCUCUCCUCGACACUGCAACUCCUGGCCAUGGCACUGGAGUGCUGGCUCUCCCUAGGGCACCCUUUCUUCUACCGACGGCACAUCACCCUGCGCCUGGGCGCACUGGUGGCCCCGGUGGUGAGCGCCUUCUCCCUGGCUUUCUGCGCGCUACCUUUCAUGGGCUUCGGGAAGUUCGUGCAGUACUGCCCCGGCACCUGGUGCUUUAUCCAGAUGGUCCACGAGGAGGGCUCGCUGUCGGUGCUGGGGUACUCUGUGCUCUACUCCAGCCUCAUGGCGCUGCUGGUCCUCGCCACCGUGCUGUGCAACCUCGGCGCCAUGCGCAACCUCUAUGCGAUGCACCGGCGGCUGCAGCGGCACCCGCGCUCCUGCACCAGGGACUGUGCCGAGCCGCGCGCGGACGGGAGGGAAGCGUCCCCUCAGCCCCUGGAGGAGCUGGAUCACCUCCUGCUGCUGGCGCUGAUGACCGUGCUCUUCACUAUGUGUUCUCUGCCCGUAAUUUAUCGCGCUUACUAUGGAGCAUUUAAGGAUGUCAAGGAGAAAAACAGGACCUCUGAAGAAGCAGAAGACCUCCGAGCCUUGCGAUUUCUAUCUGUGAUUUCAAUUGUGGACCCUUGGAUUUUUAUCAUUUUCAGAUCUCCAGUAUUUCGGAUAUUUUUUCACAAGAUUUUCAUUAGACCUCUUAGGUACAGGAGCCGGUGCAGCAAUUCCACUAACAUGGAAUCCAGUCUGUGACAGUGUUUUUCACUCUGUGCUACCUAUUACAGCCGUAUUCUGCUGUCCGUGGAGACGGUAAGAUCUUAGGUUCCAAGAUUUUACUUCAAAUUACACCUUCAAAACUGGAGCAGCAUAUAGCCGAAAAGGAGCACAACUGAGCACUUUAAUAGUAAUUUAAAAGUUUUCAAGGGUCAGCAAUAUGAUGACUGAAAGGGAAAAGUGGAGGAAACGCAGCUGCAACUGAAGCGGAGACUCUAAACCCAGCUUGCAGGUAAGAGCUUUCACCUUUGGUAAAAGAACAGCUGGGGAGGUUCAAGGGGUUUCAGCAUCUCUGGAGUUCCUUUGUAUCUGACAAUCUCAGGACUCCAAGGUGCAAAGCCUGCUGCAUUUGCGUGAUCUCAAGACCUCCAGCCAGAAGUCCCUUCCAAAUAUAAGAGUACUCAUGUUUAUUUAUUUCCAACUGAGCAGCAACCUCCUUUGUUUCACUUAUGUUUUUUCCAGUAUCUGAGAUAAUAUAAAGCUGGGUAAUUUUUUAUGUAAUUUUUUGGUAUAGCAAAACUGUGAAAAAGCCAAAUUAGGCAUACAAGGAGUAUGAUUUAACAGUAUGACAUGAUGAAAAAAAUACAGUUGUUUUUGAAAUUUAACUUUUGUUUGUACCUUCAAUGUGUAAGUACAUGCAUGUUUUAUUGUCAGAGGAAGAACAUGUUUUUUGUAUUCUUUUUUUGGAGAGGUGUGUUAGGAUAAUUGUCCAGUUAAUUUGAAAAGGCCCCAGAUGAAUCAAUAAAUAUAAUUUUAUAGUAUUUUGCAGAGGAAAUUACUUUUCUUUAAAUGAAAGAAAAGGGCUUGGCUUUCUUUUUAGUAGACAGUUGCCAGCAAUAUUUCAUUGUCUGGCAGUUUCCUAGUGUGGAUUUUUAUAUACUGUCCGAUUAACACUUACAUUACUUUAAACAAGCUUUCAUUACUUUACUUACAUUUCAUUACUUUACAUUACUUUAAACAAGCUUAGGUAAGUCCUUAGACUCACCUAAGGACCUAGUGCUCCUUUUUGUUUCAUACAAAAUGUAGAUAUACCAUCUGGAUGAAGUCUGUGUUGAGUUAAAACCAACUCUUCGGUAAUCUGUAUAGAUUUAUUCAUUAAUUCAUUAAAUAAUUUACAGAGACCUUGUGCCAAGCAGUUGAUUAGGGGCUGAGGAAAGGAAUAAAAAUAAGACUCAAUCAUGGUUCAUGAGUUGCUCGUUGUCCACUGGGGUAGAGAGGAAUGUCAACAGUUAGGAUACAGCAUAGAAAUUCUCCAUAGUAUUGCGAGUACGCAUUUACUAUUAGAAGAGGAGGCCCAAACUAGGGACCACGUGUAGGGUUGUCAGGAGAACUUCACAGGAAGAAGAUGCAUUGAAAGUCAAGUAUUGAAAACGAGUAGGAAUUUUGACUCUGAAAACUGAAAAGAACACAGAGAAAGUUUACAUAAGAGAAAAUACAUAUGGUUAAUAAAUGUAGAAAAAUAUUCAGCCUAAUCAAGGAAAUGCAAAAAUAAAACCAAAUUGUAUAUCAACAACAAGCAACAACAACAACAAAAAACCUAUGACUCUCAAUAACAGAGGUUAUUCAGAGAAGAACAUUCAUGUUCCCCUGGCGAGUUCGUAAAUGUGUAUACCCUUUCUUGAUAGCAACCCAACAGUGUAUCAAGAACCUAAAGCGUUCUUUGCUGUUGUUCCAGUAAUUCCACUCUAGCAUUCUCUUGCAGAGAAUAAUCAGUAGUCCUGGACAAGCAGCAGUAGCAACACCUGAAACUUACUACAAAUGCAAAUUCUCCAGCUCCACGUCAGACCUGUUGAAUCAGAAUCUCUUGGGUGGGGCCAGCAAUCUGGGCUUUAACAUGCCCUCCAGGUGAUUCUCAUGCAUGCUAAUAUUUGAGAACCACUGCUCUACACAAAACAAAAAAAGAAAAGAAAAGAAAAAUACCAAAAAAAGACAAGUAAAUAUGUGAUAGACUAUGUUUCUCUGACCUCUGAUUCUCAGAUCCUUUCAGUUGCAGAUAAUCCCUCACACCUGAACUUCCACAGUGUUUUUAUCUGUAAUGUUCUCAGCAAAGUUACAGCUUUGUAAACUAGUUCAACCAUUGUGGAAGUCAGUGUGGCAAUUCCUCAGGGAUCUAGAACUAGAAAUACCAUUUCACCCAGCCAUCCCAUUACCGGGUAUAUACCCAAAGGAUUAUAAAUCAUGCUGCUAUAAAAACACAUGCACACGUAUGUUUAUAGUGGCACUAUUCACAAGAGCAAAUACUUGGAACCAACCUAAAUGUCCAACAAUGAUAGACUGGAUUAAGAAAAUGUGGCACAUAUACACCAUGGAAUACUAUGCAGCCAUAAAGAAUGAUGAGUUCAUGUCCUUUGUAGGGACAUGGAUGAAACUGGAAACCAUCAUUCUCAGCAAACUAUCGCAAAGACAAAAAUCCAAACACCACAUGUUCUCACUCAUAGGUGGGAAUUGAACAAUGAGAACACAUGGACACAGGAAGGGGAACAUCACACACCGGGGACUGUUGUGGGGUGGGGGGAGCUGGGAGAGAUAGCAUUAGGAGAUAUACCUAAUGUAAAUGACGAGUUAAUGGGUGCAGCACACCAACAUGGCACAGGUAUACAUAUGUAACAAACCUGCACGUUGUGCACAGGUACCCUAAAACUUAAAGUAUAAUAAUAAUAAAGUUUUAAAAAAAAGAAAAAAAAUAAUAUAUCUUUCAAUACUGGCAGCCAUUACUGAUUCCCAAGUUCAUCACUGAUAGCAGUGAUGAGACCUGUCUUGCUCACUUGGAGGUAAAGAUACUACCCUCGGCAAUGAUAUUUCUUUGGACUGCUGCAGACAUUUAAUUGGGCACUAAGCCUGAUGCUGUUGUGAAGGAAGAUAAACUAAAGAGCCUUUGUUUAUGAAAAUAUUGUCAAAGAUUAUAUUUAAAGUGAGCUUUCAUUAGGGAUUGAAUAUUUUCUAACUCUCUAUAGGAUAGAAAUUUCCAUUGAAAUACGUAAAGCUAUUUUUAAACUUUCAUAAUUUGACUUUUUUGUAUAUUUUCAGGAAAAUAUUAUACAUUGAAUCUUUCUUUCCAGGCAUUAAAAUCCUUGAGGACUAGAUAGUCACCUAUUUUUUUCUCAUUUCUCCUAGUAAUUCACAUAUAUACUGUAGAAGAGCUAUAAAUAUACUAUAAAUAUAUUGAAUAAAACGCGUUCUCUCUCAUGAUAGUCCUAAAAUGUACGUCUAUUCAAUAAGAGGCUGCUGUAUGCUUGGUUAAAGAUUCCUCUGUAUCUGAUGAAGAAUGUUCUCAUAUCACCAUAUAAGGAUUUUUCUCUUAGGCCAACCAAAGGUGAAAAUAGUACACGUAGGAGAAAAUAUUUUUGCUCUAUAUUAUUUCCCACUGUUAUCGACAUUAUGUAAGUUAACAUGUAUGUUUCAAUUUUUAUCCAGGAAAUAGCAACUCGUACAUGAUGAAAUUAACAACAUAAAAAGUUUGUUAAUUAGGCAAUGUUAACAUUGUAAAAACAACUUUGUCUUAUUAGAACAGUGUUGACUGGCCUGCUCUUUAAUUAUUUUCUUCAGUGAGGCUAGGAUUGCUGGUCUGGGUGUUCCCAGACUCUAGGUGGAGGAAAGCUGAGCACAUAGGAUGGGUGGUACUAUAAUUAGGCUUCCUCUCUCUACCGUUUCACAAUAGCCAAAUUCAGUGGAAUGAAUCAGCAGAUCUCGCCUGAUAACAGUGAGGUGAACAUUCUAGUCUUCCAGAUAUUUUUAUACAAACUGCACGAACUCAGGAGUAAGUCCAAUCAUAACAAACCUGCAUGUUGUGCACAUGUACCCUAAAACUUAAAGUAUAAUAAUAAUAAAAUUAAAAAAAAAAUUGCAAUGAAUGUGUUUAGAACCGAUCAUGCUCUGGUUAAAAAUACAGGGAGAAGAUAUAAGCUUUUUUUUUUUCCUACUAAAAUGCCUCAACCGGGGAAGGCAAUAAAAAUACAGUCAAGUCAAAGCUCAAAUGAAAGUAUAUUUUAGGCAAAGCAUAGGGUCCUAUGAUGAUCUUAAACUGAGUAAGCACUUGGAAUCUAAUUGGAAACACAGGACAAACUAGAAGGUAAAAAUCAUACAGUGUAGUGCAAAUGUUACAAAGUACUAAAGUAUGAGUUAUAGAUUUUAAAACAAUAAAGCCCCAAAUCAGCGAUAAUUGAUGUUUAAGAUUAGUCUAGCGGUGCGUUGUAUAAACACCUGGGCAAACAAAGUUGGUAGCUUGCCAGCAUCAAUUUCUUAUCACUACAAAAUAGAAUAUGGAAACAAUAACUGUCAUGACACACAAUUCAUAAUGAAUUUAGAAAAUACUUUUUAUUCCCCCCAAAUUAAAAAACACCCAGAGUUCCCAAUUAGAUGAAAAAGAUAAAGUACAAUGAUUUACUGAUUAUGAUUGUGUGAAAGUAAAAUAAAUCUUGGGACCCCAAACUCACUAAACCAAACAGAAACGUCAAGCUGGGAACUGGGUCACGCCAACCUGCAUCUCAUUUUGGUUCCUAAAUAAGAUGGCUAAAAUACGAAAAGCUACAUACCUCCUUCACAUUUUGUCCACACGGAAAUUCCUUGGGGGCCCCAAGACCUUUUUCCUAAAGUGUUUCUGUUAGAGUGCAUCAUGGCAAUGUGAAUGGAUAGCUUUUCUCCACAGGUGUGGGGACAUAGGAGAGAACUCAGUCAUCCCUCUGUCCACCUGAGACAAAUGCAUAUCUGAUUGUUUCCUCUGCUCUAUCGUCUGCAUUAUCUACAUAUGUAAAAAUGCAGAUUCACUGAGCCAGACAAAGGCAUGAAUGACUGUUUUCCCCUACCCUCUUCUCACAUGAAAAUUAUGUAUUUCUCAAUAUCCUUCCCUUUCCCCUUUAGAUAUUGAAACCCUCAAAAUCAUCUAUGGGGAAAGGAAUAGACCUAUCUCCCAGGUGUGUAUCCUUAACUUUGGCAAAUAAACCUCAAAAAAUGA